AAUUCUGAAAGCCGCUGGCGGACCGCGCGCAGCGGCCAGAGACCGAGCCCUAAGGAGAGUGCGGCGCUUCCCGAGGCGUGCAGCUGGGAACUGCAACUCAUCUGGGUUGUGCGCAGAAGGCUGGGGCAAGCGAGUAGAGAAGUGGAGCGUAAGCCAGGGGCGUUGGGGGCCGUGCGGGUCGGGCGCGUGCCACGCCCGCGGGGUGAAGUCGGAGCGCGGGGCCUGCUGGAGAGAGGAGCGCUGCGGACCGAGUAAUGGCAAUGCAGAUGCAGCUUGAAGCAAAUGCAGAUACUUCAGUGGAAGAAGAAAGCUUUGGCCCACAACCCAUUUCACGGUUAGAGCAGUGUGGCAUAAAUGCCAACGAUGUGAAGAAAUUGGAAGAAGCUGGAUUCCAUACUGUGGAGGCUGUUGCCUAUGCGCCAAAGAAGGAGCUAAUAAAUAUUAAGGGAAUUAGUGAAGCCAAAGCUGAUAAAAUUCUGACGGAGUCUCGCUCUGUUGCCAGGCUGGAGUGCAAUAGCGUGAUCUUGGUCUACUGCACCCUCCGCCUCUCAGGUUCAAGUGAUUCUCCUGCCUCAGCCUCCCGAGUAGUUGGGACUACAGGUGGAAUUGAGACUGGAUCUAUCACAGAAAUGUUUGGAGAAUUCCGAACUGGGAAGACCCAGAUCUGUCAUACGCUAGCUGUCACCUGCCAGCUUCCCAUUGACCGGGGUGGAGGUGAAGGAAAGGCCAUGUACAUUGACACUGAGGGUACCUUUAGGCCAGAACGGCUGCUGGCAGUGGCUGAGAGGUAUGGUCUCUCUGGCAGUGAUGUCCUGGAUAAUGUAGCAUAUGCUCGAGCGUUCAACACAGACCACCAGACCCAGCUCCUUUAUCAAGCAUCAGCCAUGAUGGUAGAAUCUAGGUAUGCACUGCUUAUUGUAGACAGUGCCACCGCCCUUUACAGAACAGACUACUCGGGUCGAGGUGAGCUUUCAGCCAGGCAGAUGCACUUGGCCAGGUUUCUGCGGAUGCUUCUGCGACUCGCUGAUGAGUUUGGUGUAGCAGUGGUAAUCACUAAUCAGGUGGUAGCUCAAGUGGAUGGAGCAGCGAUGUUUGCUGCUGAUCCCAAAAAACCUAUUGGAGGAAAUAUCAUCGCCCAUGCAUCAACAACCAGAUUGUAUCUGAGGAAAGGAAGAGGGGAAACCAGAAUCUGCAAAAUCUACGACUCUCCCUGUCUUCCUGAAGCUGAAGCUAUGUUCGCCAUUAAUGCAGAUGGAGUGGGAGAUGCCAAAGACUGAAUCAUUGGGUUUUUCCUCUGUUAAAAACCUUAAGUGCUGCAGCCUAAUGAGAGUGCACUGCUCCCUGGGGUUCUCUACAGGCCUCUUCCUGUUGUGACUGCCAGGAUAAAGCUUCCGGGAAAACAGCUAUUAUAUCAGCUUUUCUGAUGGUAUAAACAGGAGACAGGUCAGUAGUCACAAACUGAUCUAAAAUGUUUAUUCCUUCUGUAGUGUAUUAAUCUCUGUGUGUUUUCUUUGGUUUUGGAGGAGGGGUAUGAAGUAUCUUUGACAUGGUGCCUUAGGAAUGACUUGGGUUUAACAAGCUGUCUACUGGACAAUCUUAUGUUUCCAAGAGAACUAAAGCUGGAGAGACCUGACCCUUCUCUCACUUCUAAAUUAAUGGUAAAAUAAAAUGCCUCAGCUAUGUAGCAAAGGGAAUGGGUCUGCACAGAUUCUUUUUUUCUGUCAGUAAAACUCUCAAGCAGGUUUUUAAGUUGUCUGUCUGAAUGAUCUUGUGUAAGGUUUUGGUUAUGGAGUCUUGUGCCAAACCUACUAGGCCAUUAGCCCUUCACCAUCUACCUGCUUGGUCUUUCAUUGCUAAGACUAACUCAAGAUAAUCCUAGAGUCUUAAAGCAUUUCAGGCCAGUGUGGUGUCUUGCGCCUGUACUCCCAGCACUUUGGGAGGCCGAGGCAGGUGGAUCGCUUGAGCCCAGGAGUUUUAAGUCCAGCUUGGCCAAGGUGGUGAAAUCCCAUCUCUACAAAAAAUGCAGAACUUAAUCUGGACACACUGUUACACGUGCCUGUAGUCCCAGCUACUCGAUAGCCUGAGGUGGGAGAAUCACUUAAGCCUGGAAGGUGGAAGUUGCAGUGAGUCGAGAUUGCACUGCUGCAUUCCAGCCAGGGUGACAGAGUGAGACCAUGUUUCAAACAAGAAACAUUUCAGAGGGUAAGUAAACAGAUUUGAUUGUGAGGCUUCUAAUAAAGUAGUUAUUAGUAGUGAAUGUGCUGUUUAUAGCAAUUAUUGCAGUGCAAGCUAUUUCAAGACAGGGUUUCCAUAAUCUUUUUGGCACUGUAUAGGGGUGAUCAGUUUCUGUUGCUUCAAGAUUUGAAACCAGAAAGGAAAGUCCCACUUGCAGAUGAUUGUGCUUAAAAGCUAAUGGAAAAAUAAAAGAAAGACAUACCA